CCGGGCCGGGCCGGGACCAAGCGCUCGGAGCCCCCGCGGGACUACGUGUCCCGGGAGGGGGCCCCGCGGCUGGGGCCGGGGCCCUGGGACAAUGGUGGGGAGCGGCGGCCGGCCGGCACCCCGCGGCUCCGCGAGGGAAUUCGCCGAGAGCUCUGCGCGAGGGAAUGAAUUGUUUGGCAAAUGGAUGUUGCGCGCGGGAGCCGCUACUCUUUCCCCAGGGAGUGGUUGAUUCAUUGAGUCCGCAGACUCUUUUUUUUAAAAAAUUACUAUUGAUCCUGGAAAGAGAGACUGCUUGUCUUUGAGGACGCGAGCGGCGAUGCCCCGCGCCUUGGACGCCCAGGCCGGAUGGCUGCCUGCCUGGCGCAGAGCGAGGGCCCGGGGUUCACAAGGGGAGGGUUUGCGCGGGCCUGGCCGCGGAGCCCCGAGCCGUUCACGUUCCGCCUGCCAGGGUCCCUCGUUUCGGUUUGCAGAACUGUCCAGCGGCAGAGAAAGGUCGCACUCAAAGGCACACCCACCUGUCCACCUGGGUGGCGGCCAGACUGGCAGGUCCAGAGCAAGCCCUCUAGCCUGACUCUAAUUACCACACUUGCCCUGGCUCCGAGACACACCGCGCGAUGUUACGCCCCCACUCCCCCUGUCUCUUUCGUAGUUGCUUUAGAAGCUUUUCUCUUGGGGGAUUGUGCCCGGGAGAUACCAGAUACUUUUUUUGUGUUGCUGCUCUAAGCCCCCAAAGUGCAUUCCCAUUGUCUUUGAACAAAGAAACAUCUCUCUAGAGGCCUGACCCAACGAACUGUGGGUGAGGGGGCGGACCCAGGCCCCUGCAGAUUUAAUCUGGACGCUCUUGGGUCCUGCUGGAUCCCGGUGAAUUUGACCUUGGGGAAGGCGGGCUGGACUUUGACUCUCCUCGGUAGUCAGGGCAGAGAAUGCCAGGUGUCUGGACCAUUUGGUUCCACUCUAUCGGCCCAAUAGAGAGAGGAAGGGAAGGAAGUUAGCAGUAGCACCAGGAGAGGAGGCAGGAUUCCACGGUCUGUAUCCUGGACCAGAUUCCAGUGACCGUUAUGGGGCCAAGCCCUCUGGGACCCUGGGUCCCAGUCUCCCCAUUCAUAGGAGGAACUGAUGCUCAGUGUGCUGAUCUGAGCUGUGAGGAUUCCUGGCAUGUUGGUGAAGGCUUGCGUGGGGGUCUGGGGAAGAGUAGGACACAAAGUCUACCCCACCUCAGGGUCCAUUUGGUGUCCCAAGACCGGAGGCUCUUGGGUCCACAAGCUGUGCCUGUGAAGGUUGACGUAGUCAGUCUUUUUCCGGCCUGGCAGCUAUUUCAGUUUUGAGUCAUUUGUCAGGCAGUGACUCCAGGGUGGUUGAUAAAAGGGAGGUAGAAAUGGAAGACACCUUCAUCCUGGGGUCUUGGGCUGCAGUUGGAUUUAUGUAUGUGGUGCGGAGAGAAGAGCUAUAGGCAAAUUGCAUGCUCCACAUCGGAAGCAGGUUCUGCAGCCCGAUGCCCCUUAAUAGCGUUUUAAAUCUGCGGGCACCCCGUGUGGGCAGAAGAGAGCAGGAAGAAAAGAGAACAAUUACCCAGUGAAAGCAAGCUUGGUUCGUCCCGUCUAUCACUUGGGCGGGGGCGGGGGGAAGGGUAGGAUGAGUGAGAGUGUUAUUUAGUGGGUGGUUUGUGACUGAUUGAUUGAUUGAUUCAUUGUUUGAACAGACUUGAUUGGGCACCUGCUGUGUGCCAGGCCCUGAGUUAGGUGCUGGAGACUCUUCCUUUAGUGAGCACCUAGAUGAGGGAGUGCUGGCACAUGGAUUAGGGGCCCUGACACAUCGUAGUGAUAGAGGCAGCAAGAGGAGAGAAGGAGACACAGGUGGGCAAGGCUUCCUGGGGAGAGGAUGCCUUGACUAAGAUGAGAAAGGCAUGUCAUCGCCCAGAUUCGAGGUGUAGGGCAGCCACCUUUGUCCUGUCGCUCACCCACACUUCUCCCAGAGGCCCAAUUCAUUGCCAGCCUCAAGAUAGGCACAGGUUGAGGCCAUGGAGAAUGCAAGUGGGAGGUGGUAGAAGGUUUGCUCUCGUCCGUAGUGUCUGGCCGCACAGUCAGCAGUCCAGCGCAUUUGUAGGAAGCUGGAUGGCUUCUGGAUGCAGCCUCUCUUCUCUGGGGGUCCUGGGAGAACCUACCCCCUGGUCCCAAAGACCAGCCCAUUGUCUGAGCCCCUAGUCCCUCUGUACCACCAGGCAGUGUAGGCAUAGCCUGGCCAGUGUGGGCAGAGCUGGCACAAGAAAACAGAGUGGCCAGACACAAAUGAAUUGGUUGAUUGAGAUGCUGGUUUUCAUCUAAUGUGGUAAAUUUCAUAAUUUAAUUGCCUCAGCCAGCCAAGGCUGUUGAAGCAUUUUCCUCACCAGGAAACACUUAGUUGGAACAAGCUGGGGGUAGAGGAGGGAGGUGCAGGGGAGGAGGGAGGAGGGAGAACUUAAGCAUCCACAGCUUUCAGUCACAGCAUCCCAACAGGACUUAUCAAUCAGCAGCUAUCCCCAGCUGAUGGAAGUCAGCCCAGCCCCUACAGUAGGUUCCAACCCCUUUCCUUGACCACCUCAUUGCCAUACCAACCUAAAGCUGUCAAAAGCUGACACCUGUCAUCUUCAAGGCAUAAUCAUCCCAUACUGCCUCCAGGUCCUUCUGGGGCUGUUAGAAACUGGGGAAGGGGUGCUGUGGGAUUAGGUGGGGAAGCGAAGGGGUUUGGGGAUAGGAAGGGCUCCCUGUUAAGUCCUUUUAACCCAGGAGCAGUGGAAAGAGCAUGGGCUUUGGCACCAGACUGGGGUUCAAAUGCUGUGGGUCUGUGAUCAAGUUCCUUAACCUCAUUGAGCUUUGUUAGCUUUUUUCAGGGGUAUGGUGAAGGUUAACCACCAUACUAUGCAGAAUCCCCUAGAAUGGGGUCUGGCACCAAGUGGGUGUCAGUCAUGCCGGGCUCCCCUUUCCCUUUUUUGUUUUUGUUCCCUGGGUGCAGAAUUGAGGUUGGGUGCUUGUUGCUCUGCAGCUGACUUGCAGCCCUCCCCUGAGUCCCCAGUCACCUCACCCCCGCCCCCUACCUCUCUUGCCACUCUUUCUUACUGCUAAACCUUUCCUGCUUUCCUUCCAAGCCCUGUCCCAGCACCCUGUUGGAUGAUAAACGAUAGAUGUGUGUGGCUUAUUAACCUUUUUUUCUUUUGAGAAGGAGUCUCGCUCUGUCGCCCAGGCUGGAGUGCAAUGGCGCCAUCUUGGUUCACUGCAACUUCUGCCUCCUGGAUUCAAGUGAUUCUCCCGCCUCAGCCUCCUGAGUAGCUGGGAUUACAGGCACACACCACCAUGCCUGGCUAAUUUUUGUAUUUUUGUAGAGACGGGGUUUCUCCAUGUUGUCCAGGCUGGUCUUGAACUCCUGAUCUCAGGUGAUCCACCCGCCUCAGCCUCCUAAAGUGCUGGGAUUACAGGCAUGAGCCACUGUGCCUGGCAUUUUUCUUUUUUUUUUUUUGAGACUGAGUCUUACCUUGUAGCCCAGGCUGGAGUGCAGUGGUGUGAUCUCAGCUCACUGCAAUCUCCACCUCUCAAGUCAACCAGUUGUCUGCCUCAGCUUCCCCAGUAGCUGGGAUUACAGGCACCCGCCACCAUGCUCGGCUUUUUGUAUUUUUAGUAGAGACAGGGUUUCACCAUGUUGGCCAGGCUGGUCUUGAACUCCUGACCUCGUGAUCCACCUGCCUUGGCAUCCCAAAGUGCUGGGAUUACAGGUGUGAGCCACCGCACCUGGCCUUUUUUUUUUUUUUUUAAAUGGCAGCUCUGUGGUCUCAGAAAUCAAUUUCAUUGAGAAAUUGCACCAUAUUUUCUGCAAAUACAUAAAAAUCUUCCUGGUCAUACUUUUCUCCCACAGUGGUCUCCUGUUCCCUGAGUUGGGUACAGAGUCUGUAUGAGGCUCACCUGGGCCACUUCUUGUUUCAGCGUGACCAAGGCCCGAGGCCAACUCCGUCUCUUCACCAUCCCAUAGCUAGAGCCCUCAGACCUGGAACCUGUUGGCAGAAAGAGCACUUGAGUCAGAGUAGGGGAGUCGUGCUUGGCCCCAGCUUGCCUGUGUGACUACAUGCAGGUUCCCUUACCCCUGUGAGCCUCAAUUUGCUCUCCUGUAUAAUACUUCUAUUAAAUGUUUUGCUAUAAAAUUUCAAAAGUUCUUGCAAGCUCUGGUGUUCAGCAGUUUUAUAAGGCUCGAGUUACUUGCUUAGCCUUUCUGGUCAGGAAGAGCUUGAACAGCCAGUAGAGUACAGAGGGGCCAAUUUAGAAGUCAGGAAUGGACCGGGCGAGGUGGCUCACCCCUGUAAUCCCAGUGCUUUGGGAGGCCGAGGUGGGCGGAUCACCUGAGGUCGGGAGUUUGAGACCAGCCUGACCAACAUGGAGAAACCGCUUGUUUACUAAAAAUACGAAAUUAGCUGGGUGUGGUGGCUCAUGCCUGUAAUCCCAGCUACUUGGGAGGCUGAGGCAGGAGAAUCACUUGAACUGGGAGGCGGAGGUUGCAGCGAGCCGAGAUUGCACCAUUGCACUCCAGCCUGGGUGACAAGAGCGAAACUCCGUCUCAACAACAACAACAAAAGAAGUCAGGAAUGGGGUUCUAGUUCCAGCUCUGCCUUGGAUGUGUGCUGUGGGAAUUGGGCAAGUUACUUUCUCUGGGAUCUAGUUUUUUCACCUGUAGAGUGAGAGGGGUGACGUAGGCAAGCUCCUAGUUUCCUGAAGACUCGAUUCAGAUUUUCCCAGUAACUCCAAAGGGACGGGGCUGUUCUCCUUGAGCCUCUGGCAGUUCCCUGUCCCUGCCCACUGCCUCAGAGUUUGAGGCCUCCUGCGAAGGGGCUGGUGGAGACAGAAGACUGCAUCAGGGGAGCACCAGGCUGGGCUUAGGGGAGCAGGCGUGGGCUCAAGGGAAGGUGGUGUGUGGGUUACUCAUUUCUCAGGGCCAUCGCUCUGACUGGUCGUGGGCAGGGAGCUGGGCAGCAGUUCGUGGGAGCACCAGGAUGACCCCCUCUGGAAUGACUAGGGUGAGACUUCCCUGGUGGGAUGUCCCUUGGGCACAGAGCCAGGGCCACCUCCCAGCAGAGAGUUGGACAACGAGCUUUGAGGAGCAAGGGAGAUCUUCAGCAGAUUAGCUGGACAUGGUGGCAGGCGCCUAUAAUUCCAGCUACUUGGGAGGCUGAGACAGGAGAAUCGCUUGAACCCCGGAGGCAGAAGUUGCAGUAAGCCGAGAUCGCGCCAUGGCACUGCAGCCUGGGCAACAGAGUAAAAUUCUGUCAAAAAAAAAAAAAGGGAUCUCAAGGGAGCCCAGCAGGGCAGGAGGAGGCGACUGAGCACCAGCCUGCAAGACCAGUUGGAUGGCUCCUCCCACGGGGAAGCAGGGCUGAGCAGGCCAUGGGAGCGCUGUGCCUGCUGCCACCAGCUCAAGGGCCACAUUCACCUUAGGUGUCACUCCCCACCCAUCUCUGCCAGGAGGAGCCUUCCACCAUCAGCCGAGUGGUGAGGAGUAGGAUGCAGGGAAAGGAUGGAGACAAAAAAGCCUUGCUUACAUUUUUUGCCUGUUCCCAUUGGGCCCCCAAGGAGAGGCUGACCACAGAUCCAUCUAGGCUGAGCAGAAUUAAUUUCCUAAUUAAGAUAAGGAGAAGCUGUGCUCAUUCAAACUCCAGGACAAGCUGCCAGCCAGGUUUGCUGUUGGCCAGGCCAAUUUGUCUGAGAGGAGUGAGGGCCAAGAGAUGGAGGAGCUCUUUUUCUAGAAAACCAUGGCGAUUCCAUCCAUUGUCCGGAGUUCAUGUUCUGCACCCUAGCCAGCUGGGCUUGUGAGACCUUGGCAGCAAGUCCCUUAACCUGUGAACGCUUUUGUUGUUCACAGGCUUGGAAAUCUGAGGGAGAAAGGUACCCAGCUUUGUUCAUGCAACAAACAUUUAUUUAGUUUUCUGAAUGGCUCGCCGUGGACUAGAAGCUGAGGAAAGAAAGUCAGGUUCAAAGAGCUCCUGCUUGGGAGCUCAGCGUCUGAUGUGGGAGGCAGACAGGCGGGUAUGGCACAGCGCUAGGGUCUCAAUAGUGGGCAUGUUGAGAAUCUGCCUCAGUUUCCUCAUUGAUGAGGUGAGGAAGUGGACUGUUGGUUUCCUCAUUUCAAAUGUGUCCAGGGAAUUUUUUUCCCCCAUCUGUUCUCUGCCGGGCUCUGGGAUUCAGUGGAGAACAAGGCAAGGUCCUCCCCGACCCUCUCCUGAUCCCACAUUCAGCUGAGGGAGGCAGACAACAGACUGACAAAAAUAUGCAGCUGCAGAGGAAGUGGACAGGGAGGUGUGGGAAGAUGGUCAAGUGAGGAUGCCCUCCGAAGAGGGGUCAAGGAAGGCCUCUCUGGGGUGGUGACAUUUGAGCCAGCCGUGGGAGGAUCAGAGAAAGGCCUGCCAGGUGGGUAGCACAGCUCGUGCAAAGGCUGGGCCUGCGUGGGCUGCGGACAGAGACAUCAUGAGGCACAGAGAGGUGCCAGACCCUGACAUUCUGCAGUCUUCUGGUGCAGGGAGAGACUGAGGAUAACAUUGUUCUCUUUCAUUUUAUUGUUUUUCUCUGAUUUAAAUAAUAUAUCAAUGGAUUUCCUUUUUUUUUUUUUUUUUUUUUUGAGAUCUAGUUUCCCUCUCAUUGCCCAGGCCGCAGUGCGGUGGCGCGAUCUCAGCUCACCUCCGCUUCCCGGGUUCAAGCAAUUCUCCUGCCUCAGCCUCCCAAGUAGCUGGGAUUACAGGCGCAAGCCACCACGCCCAGCUAGGAUUUCCUUUAUAAAUGAAAAAUAUAGGAAAAGAUGGAGCACAGUGUGAGGGUCCAUCCCCUCCUUUGUAUCUGUCCACAGAUGGGUGCAUACCCUUCUAGUCCUCCGUUGUAUGUGCAGAUUUUGUGUUUACAUAAUUUGAAUCAUACUCAAUACUCUACAACUUAUACCACUUAGUGUGUGGUGGAGCUCUUUUUCACAGCGUCGUCAUAUUCCACACUGCAGCCAAACCAUCAUUUCCUCUCAUUGUGUCCUAAGGAGAGACUUUAGGUAAUGCCUCAUUUUCCCUGUAUGAUCAAUGAAAUCUUGUGUGUCCUUCAUCAUGCAUCUUUCUGAGCAAGUGUGAUUAUUUUAAAUUUUCAUUGUCAAAGCCAAAUGCCCUUUGCAAAGAUUUACCCAGUUUACUCUUUCACUAAUAAUAGUGCCUGAAUGCCCAUUUCUCUACAGACUCACCUAAUUUUUUUUUGAGACUGAGUUUCGCUCUUGUCACCCAGGCUGGAGUGCAAUGGCAUGAUCUCAGGUUACAGCAACCUCUGCCUCCCAGGUUCAAGCGAUUCUCCUGCCUCAGCCUCCCAAGUAGCUGGGAUUACAGGCAAGCGCCACCACGCCCAGCUAAUUUUGUAUUUUUAGUAGAGACUGGGUUUCUCCAUGUUGGCCAGGCUGGUCUCAAACUCCUGACCUCAGGUGAUCCACCUGCCUCGGCCUCCCAAAGUUCUGGGAUUACAGGCGUGAGCCACUGCGCCCAGCCCCCAAAUUUUUGAUGUUAUCCACAUUUUUAGUUUUAGCUAAUGUGAUGGGGUGGGGGGGCGGGUGGAAUCUCAUUGUUCCAUUAAAAAAAAUGUUUAUUCAGGCUUUGUCCUUUGAUUCUAGUCCACUUUUGUCUUUCCAGAAGAUCAAAGUUUAUUGAGUGCUGGUUCUGCCUCUUAUUGGUCUCCUGACCUCAGCUGGGUACUCAUCUGUGAAAUGAAGCCCUUUAAUCCCUGCCCGCCCCUGCCCCCCACUAGGCUGCUGUAUUUUUUGCAUGGGAAAACAUUCCUGAAAGUUCAUUUUAUGCUGAAAAGCUCUGCAAACAUGAAGAGGCAUGGUUUUUACUAGCGAAAUGGAAAUAUCUGGAACAUUUGAGUGAAUUCAGGUGUUUCUAAACAGCCAGCAUAUCCAGGGGAGGAGCUGGGGUGACUUUGCCCUUGUGCAGUGGAGCUGGCCUUAGGUGGGAGGUGUCUGCCUAUUGUCCCAGAGAUGCACGGGGCCUUACCUGGCUGAGAGCCAUCUGGCUGGGCUUGAGAGCUCUUCUCAGAGGGCUGGCUUAGUCAAUGAUCUGUCACCUGUCUGCAGGAAUAAAGAAAUGAGCCAGGAGGACAGAGAGAGUUCCGUAGCUGGUCCAGAGAAAGGCCCAGAAAGGGGCAGUGGCCACCACAGACUAAACCCUGUUUACUUGCCUGUGUGGUCCCAGGAGGCAUCGGGCCCCAUGAUAGAGGAGCCAGGGAACUGCUGACCAUGGCCUGGGCCCCAGAGGAAUUCAUUACUGCUGGGUACCUGGGGACGUUUUGGCCAGGCUCUCCCCACCCUUCAGGAAGCAACAUCCAGGUUUGGCCAUGACUCCCCUGCUGCCCUGGAGAUGACUCAGAACCAAGCUUCAGAGGAGGCUCCUGUGAUCCCAGCCAGCCUGACCUACUUGGAACAAUCUCAGGGACAGAUCUGACGCACCAUGUCGGUCAGUGUCCAUGAGACCCGCAAGUCGCGGAGCAGCACGGGGUCCAUGAACGUCACCCUCUUCCACAAGGCCUCCCACCCGGACUGUGUGCUGGCCCACCUCAACACGCUUCGCAAGCACUGCAUGUUCACCGACGUCACACUCUGGGCGGGCGACCGUGCCUUCCCCUGUCACCGUGCCGUGCUGGCCGCCUCUAGCCGCUAUUUUGAGGCCAUGUUCAGCCAUGGCCUUCGGGAGAGCCGGGAUGACACUGUCAACUUCCAGGACAACCUGCACCCGGAGGUGCUGGAGCUGCUGCUGGACUUUGCCUACUCCUCACGCAUCGCCAUCAACGAGGAGAACGCUGAGUCACUGCUGGAGGCAGGCGACAUGCUGCAGUUCCACGAUGUGCGGGAUGCUGCCGCCGAGUUCCUGGAGAAGAACCUUUUCCCCUCCAACUGCCUGGGCAUGAUGCUGCUCUCGGACGCCCACCAGUGCCGCCGGCUGUAUGAGUUCUCCUGGCGCAUGUGCCUGGUGCACUUUGAGACGGUGAGGCAGAGCGAGGACUUCAACAGCCUGUCCAAGGACACACUGCUGGACCUCAUCUCGAGUGAUGAGCUGGAGACCGAGGACGAGCGGGUGGUCUUCGAGGCCAUCCUCCAGUGGGUGAAGCACGACCUGGAGCCACGGAAGGUCCACUUGCCCGAGCUCCUCCGCAGCGUGCGUCUGGCCUUGCUGCCGUCCGACUGCCUGCAGGAGGCCGUCUCCAGCGAGGCCCUCCUCAUGGCAGACGAGCGCACCAAGCUUAUCAUGGAUGAGGCCCUGCGCUGCAAGACCAGGAUCCUGCAGAAUGAUGGCGUGGUCACCAGCCCCUGUGCCCGGCCACGCAAGGCGGGCCACACGCUACUCAUCCUGGGGGGCCAGACCUUCAUGUGUGACAAGAUCUACCAGGUGGACCACAAGGCCAAGGAGAUCAUCCCCAAGGCCGACCUGCCCAGCCCCCGGAAGGAGUUCAGCGCCUCAGCGAUCGGCUGCAAGGUCUAUGUGACGGGGGGCAGGGGCUCCGAGAACGGGGUCUCCAAGGAUGUCUGGGUGUACGACACCGUACAUGAGGAAUGGUCCAAGGCGGCGCCCAUGCUGAUUGCCCGCUUUGGCCAUGGCUCAGCUGAGCUGGAGAACUGCCUCUAUGUGGUGGGGGGACACACAUCCCUGGCAGGGGUCUUCCCGGCCUCGCCUUCUGUCUCCCUGAAACAAGUGGAGAAAUACGACCCUGGGGCCAACAAGUGGAUGAUGGUGGCCCCCUUGCGGGAUGGCGUCAGCAAUGCCGCAGUGGUGAGUGCCAAGCUGAAGCUCUUUGUUUUCGGAGGAACCAGCAUCCACCGGGACAUGGUGUCCAAGGUCCAGUGCUAUGACCCCUCGGAGAACAGGUGGACGAUCAAGGCCGAGUGCCCCCAGCCUUGGCGGUACACAGCCGCUGCCGUCCUGGGCAGCCAGAUCUUCAUCAUGGGAGGUGACACGGAAUUCACAGCCGCCUCGGCCUACCGCUUUGACUGUGAGACCAACCAGUGGACGCGGAUUGGGGACAUGACUGCCAAGCGCAUGUCCUGCCAUGCCCUGGCUUCCGGCAACAAGCUCUAUGUGGUCGGGGGCUACUUUGGGACCCAGAGGUGUAAGACUCUGGACUGCUAUGACCCCACUUCAGAUACAUGGAACUGCAUCACCACAGUGCCCUACUCACUUAUCCCCACGGCCUUUGUCAGCACCUGGAAGCACCUGCCCGCGUGAGGAGCACCUGCUGAGCCCAGCCAGACCGCGGCCUUCAGUGUCACAGCGUGGCCUUGCUUGUCUGCCACAGCGGGAGCUAAGCCGGCCCUGGGCCAGCACUCCGAGAGGUGGAAGGGGCCCUGCCAGCUCUGGGGAGCAGCAGCCUUGGGCUGUUCUGAGCUUUAGGCAAGAGAAGAGAAGCAUCUCUUGCAUCCGUGCCCCUGGGGGCCUCUUCAGCUUUGCAGUGGUUUGUGGGAAGACAUACCUCCCAGAGGGGCAUGGACUGCCACCAGGACUGACCCUGGCGUCGGGGAGAAGGACACUUGCAGAGCCUUGAGAUCACCUGUUUGGCAGGUCCUGGACUGGGGCCGGGCAGGCAGGGGCAGGGAGGCGCCCCGGGUGGGCUUUGGGGCUGCGGCACUGCCACACAUCCUUUCCCUCCUGGCCUGCCCUGCUGGGGCUCUACUGCCAUCUAUAGAUGGUGUCCUGGGCCUGGGAAACUAGGUUCCCAGGGGUUGAGACCAGAAAGGUGACCAAGACAGAUUUUUUAAGGUGCAGAAACUGCAGGGGGGCCUCAGUGACAUCCAUGAGGCCUUAUUAGCAAAGGACACCCAGACCUCCAAGGUUUGUGGGCCCCUUCCACAAAGCUGUAAGUCCCAGCCCACCUACUCAGGGCCUUGCUCAGUGCUGUGGCCCGGUGGGGACACAGUUGCUCGUGGCCACUCAGUGGAGCUGGGCCUGCAGCAGACUCAAGGCUCCGAGUGCCCUGGGGGUCACCCCUCCCCUCCCCUCCUCAGAGCCCACCCUGAGAGGCAGCAGUGACCCCCAUGGCACACACCUGCCAACAGCACUGGGGGCUUCUCCCCAGGAGACCACGCUGCCCUCCAAGACCAGGAGCAGCUGUGAGCUGGAGACAGCAGAGGGACCCCAGGGUGUCCCCUGCAGAUCCCACCAGGGCCGCAUCCAUCUCAGUGUGGAGGACAGUGACGGGACCCUCACCAUCCUCUUGCGUUUUGGCCCCCAUUUGCUCCCUGAGCUCCAAGAUAAGAAUGGCCCCGAGAGAACUGCUGAACAUUUGUUCAUUGCUGUCACCUCCUGAGUCACUGGGGUCCCUCACCAGCACCUCCCUGACACCUGGGCUAUGGAGAGGUUGGCGCCUGUCAGUGACCAUCCUAAUGCCUCUCGCUCACUCCCAAGCCACCAUUUGAGAGGGAGGGGUGUUGGUGCCCUGACAGGGACUGGGCAGGGUGUCCAAACUUGGGGCUUCCCAGGCACCUGCAGUGUGAACACUGCUUGGCUGGCUCAAGAUUAGGGCCGCGGAGGGGGCUGUGCACAUACCAGUUACUUAAGCAGCCACGAGUGUCCCCCAUGCCUUGGUGCGGGUCCUGGAGGCCUCUUGGGGGUGGGACCUUUGGGCAGGGUUUGCCCACUGACACGCCCGCCAUGGGGCACUGGCUGCAUGGGGCUCCUUGGACCCUGUAGACCCAGCAGACCCCGCCUGUGUCAGGCCAGCUGCCCGAAGGCACUUGGCUGUGGUCCCAGGGGACGGCUCUGCUGGCACACUCAGGAGCCUGGCCGCGGGGACUGCAGGGAGGGUGCCUGGACCCGUGGGGUUGCUUCAUUGAGAUAAAGCACACUUAUCACAUAGCACAAAGGACGUGCCAUGGUGCUUUCCCCAAAAGUUGUGUUGCUUUUAUCAGUUUUCUAACUUAAUAAAAAGAGUUGAGAAAA